GAAGGCUGUCGUUGCCUUGGCCGUCGCAUCCCCGAGGGAGUCGUGUCGGCGCCACCCCGGCCCCCGAGCCCGCAGAUUGCCCACCGAAGCUCGUGUGUGCACCCCCGAUCCCGCCAGCCACUCGCCCCUGGCCUCGCGGGCCGUGUCUCCGGCAUCAUGUGUGGUAUAUUUGCUUACUUAAACUACCAUGUUCCUCGAACGAGACGAGAAAUCCUGGAGACCCUAAUCAAAGGCCUUCAGAGACUGGAGUACAGAGGAUAUGAUUCUGCUGGUGUGGGAUUUGAUGGAGGCAAUGAUAAAGAUUGGGAAGCCAAUGCCUGCAAAAUCCAGCUUAUUAAGAAGAAAGGAAAAGUUAAGGCACUGGAUGAAGAAGUUCACAAGCAACAAGAUAUGGAUUUGGAUAUAGAAUUUGAUGUACACCUUGGAAUAGCUCAUACCCGUUGGGCAACACAUGGAGAACCCAGUCCUGUCAAUAGCCACCCCCAGCGCUCUGAUAAAAAUAAUGAAUUUAUCGUUAUUCACAAUGGAAUCAUCACCAACUACAAAGACUUGAAAAAGUUUUUGGAAAGCAAAGGCUAUGACUUCGAAUCUGAAACAGACACAGAGACAAUUGCCAAGCUCGUUAAGUAUAUGUAUGACAAUCGGGAAAGUCAAGAUACCAGCUUUACUACCUUGGUGGAGAGAGUUAUCCAACAAUUGGAAGGUGCUUUUGCACUUGUGUUUAAAAGUGUUCAUUUUCCCGGGCAAGCAGUUGGCACAAGGCGAGGUAGCCCUCUGUUGAUUGGUGUACGGAGUGAACAUAAACUUUCUACUGAUCACAUUCCUAUACUCUACAGAACAGCUAGGACUCAGAUUGGAUCAAAAUUCACACGGUGGGGAUCACAGGGAGAAAGAGGCAAAGACAAGAAAGGAAGCUGCAAUCUCUCUCGUGUGGACAGCACAACCUGCCUUUUCCCGGUGGAAGAAAAAGCAGUGGAGUAUUACUUUGCUUCUGAUGCAAGUGCUGUCAUAGAACACACCAAUCGCGUCAUCUUUCUGGAAGAUGAUGAUGUUGCAGCAGUAGUGGAUGGACGUCUUUCUAUCCAUCGAAUUAAACGAACUGCAGGAGAUCACCCCGGACGAGCUGUGCAAACACUCCAGAUGGAACUCCAGCAGAUCAUGAAGGGCAACUUCAGUUCAUUUAUGCAGAAGGAAAUAUUUGAGCAGCCAGAGUCUGUCGUGAACACAAUGAGAGGAAGAGUCAACUUUGAUGACUAUACUGUGAAUUUGGGUGGUUUGAAGGAUCACAUAAAGGAGAUCCAGAGAUGCCGGCGUUUGAUUCUUAUUGCUUGUGGAACAAGUUACCAUGCUGGUGUAGCAACACGUCAAGUUCUUGAGGAGCUGACUGAGUUGCCUGUGAUGGUGGAACUAGCAAGUGACUUCCUGGACAGAAACACACCAGUCUUUCGAGAUGAUGUUUGCUUUUUCCUUAGUCAAUCAGGUGAGACAGCAGAUACUUUGAUGGGUCUUCGUUACUGUAAGGAGAGAGGAGCUUUAACUGUGGGGAUCACAAACACAGUUGGCAGUUCCAUAUCACGGGAGACAGAUUGUGGAGUUCAUAUUAAUGCUGGUCCUGAGAUUGGUGUGGCCAGUACAAAGGCUUAUACCAGCCAGUUUGUAUCCCUUGUGAUGUUUGCCCUUAUGAUGUGUGAUGAUCGGAUCUCCAUGCAAGAAAGACGCAAAGAGAUCAUGCUUGGAUUGAAACGGCUGCCUGAUUUGAUUAAGGAAGUACUGAGCAUGGAUGACGAAAUUCAGAAACUAGCAACAGAACUUUAUCAUCAGAAGUCAGUUCUGAUAAUGGGACGAGGCUAUCAUUAUGCUACUUGUCUUGAAGGGGCACUGAAAAUCAAAGAAAUUACUUAUAUGCACUCUGAAGGCAUCCUUGCUGGUGAAUUGAAACAUGGCCCUCUGGCUUUGGUGGAUAAAUUGAUGCCUGUGAUCAUGAUCAUCAUGAGAGAUCACACUUAUGCCAAGUGUCAGAAUGCUCUUCAGCAAGUGGUUGCUCGGCAGGGGCGGCCUGUGGUAAUUUGUGAUAAGGAGGAUACUGAGACCAUUAAGAACACAAAAAGAACGAUCAAGGUGCCCCACUCAGUGGACUGCUUGCAGGGCAUUCUCAGCGUGAUCCCUUUACAGUUGCUGGCUUUCCACCUUGCUGUGCUGAGAGGCUAUGAUGUUGAUUUCCCACGGAAUCUUGCCAAAUCUGUGACUGUAGAGUGAGGAAUAUCUAUACAAAAUGUACGAAACUGUAUGAUUAAGCAACACAAGACACCUUUUGUAUUUAAAACCUUGAUUUAAAAUAUCACCCCUUGAAGCCUUUUUUUAGUAAAUCCUUAUUUAUAUAUCAGUUAUAAUUAUUCCACUCAAUAUGUGAUUUUUGUGAAGUUACCUCUUACAUUUUCCCAGUAAUUUGUGGAGGACUUUGAAUAAUGGAAUCUAUAUUGGAAUCUGUAUCAGAAAGAUUCUAGCUAUUAUUUUCUUUAAAGAAUGCUGGGUGUUGCAUUUCUGGACCCUCCACUUCAAUCUGAGAAGACAAUAUGUUUCUAAAAAUUGGUACUUGUUUCACCAUACUUCAUUCAGACCAGUGAAAGAGUAGUGCAUUUAAUUGGAGUAUCUAAAGCCAGUGGCAGUGUAUGCUCAUACUUGGACAGUUAGGGAAGGGUUUGCCAAGUUUUAAGAGAAGAUGUGAUUUAUUUUGAAAUUUGUUUCUGUUUUGUUUUUAAAUCAAACUGUAAAACUUAAAACUGAAAAAUUUUAUUGGUAGGAUUUAUAUCUAAGUUUGGUUAGCCUUAGUUUCUCAGACUUGUUGUCUAUUAUCUGUAGGUGGAAGAAAUUUAGGAAGCGAAAUAUUACAGUAGUGCAUUGGUGGGUCUCAAUCCUUAACAUAUUUGCACAAUUUUAUAGCACAAACUUUAAAUUCAAGCUGCUUUGGACAACUGACAAUAUGAUUUUAAAUUUGAAGAUGGGAUGUGUACAUGUUGGGUAUCCUACUACUUUGUGUUUUCAUCUCCUAAAAGUGGUUUUUAUUUCCUUGUAUCUGUAGUCUUUUAUUUUUUAAAUGACUGCUGAAUGACAUAUUUUAUCUUGUUCUUUAAAAUCACAACACAGAGCUGCUAUUAAAUUAAUAUUGAUAUAUUCAGUAUUCUCUUCAACUUUGUCACGAGGAAGAAUUUCCUGUAGUUAAUUUUAACUUUCCUUCAUUACAUUGUUGCAUAAAACUAGUCCCUUAGUGCCAGUUUGGAAGUUACUUGCAAUUGUUUGGAAGAUUUGCAGGUCGCUGACCUCAUCAUUUCACUCUAAGUAUAUGUGGUAGGCUAAGCUCAGAAAAAGGUAUGUAUGCUUUACACUGAUAGGCACCAAAUUUAGUAUUGUAUCCUAAGUAUUUUUCCUCUUCUGUAUUUUCUGUGCUCUACCCCUGAAAUAUAUUUAGGAAUAAAGAAGAUAUAAAUAAAGUGAUAUUGGGGUAUGUUCAGCUUGUAAGUGUCAGAAAUGGAAGUUGACAAUUUGGAUUAAAAUAUUUAAAGUAGAAUGUUAUUAUUUGAUACCCCCAAAAUUGUGAGUAAUAAUUUCUUAAUGGAGCUUUUCUGGCCAGAUCUUCAGGGCUAUAGGAGAGUGUGUUUGUUUUUGGUGAAGUCCUUCUUUUUCAAAGGUUUUUACUUUUAAAUUGUGAAGAUAAGCUAUUUAGCACAAUUAUUUAAGUAAGCUGUUUUUUCCUUUCUUUUCUUUCUUUUCUUGUUUUAACUUCUGGGUGAGGUUAAGAUUUUCUAAUAGUUAUUGUUGUUGCCAGAGAAGCAUAGAAUUCUGCUUGUGUCUUAGGGUUAGAGAAAGAUUUGUUAUAUUUUGAGGUAAUUUGGAAGGACUUUCAUACAUGGUGACUAGAAACCUGAUCUUUUUAAGAAUAAAAUAGGGUCACUAUUUACAUUAUAUAUAAUAUAUGGCUAUUAUAGCUAUAUUAAUCUACUUUAAUUGUUUCUAAGAUUAUUUUGUGUAAGUCAGCUAGCGUGUGUAUAGUGUCAUUUCUUAUGUUUUGUAUAUUAACGUUUUACAAACACAAUUUGUGUGGGUUUGUAGCAUUUCUUAUAGUUUAAAGUAUGAUUCAGCAUUCUAAGUUAAAACUAAUAUGUGAAGUCAGUCAUUAGUCUGCAUAAUCUCUGUCUCCCUCUGUGUGUGUCUUUCUAUAAAGCACAUGUGUACACACACACACACAAAUAUACUGAAAGCUAGGGUAAGUUCUAAACUGAAUAUCAAAAACCAAAAUCAAGAACAAAGAAGUGAUAUUUUCCAAACAAACAUGGAUUCUCUGCCGGGUGCAGUGGCUCAGCCUGUAAUACCAGCCUCCACUUUGGGAGUCUGAGGUGGGAGUAUUGCUUGAGCUCAAGAGUUGGAGAACAGCCUGGGCAACAUGGUGAGACCUGGUCUUUACAAAAAUUUUUUUGGCCGGACGCAGUGGCUCACACCUGUAAUCCCAGCACUUUGGGAGGCCGAGGCAGGUUGAUCAUGAGGUCAAGAGAUCGAGACCAUCCUGGCCAACAUGGUGAAACCCCGUCUUUACUAAAAAUACAAAAAUUAGCUGGGAGUGGUGGCGUGCGCCUGUAGUCCCAACUACUUGGGAGGCUGAGGCAGGAGAAUCGCUUGAACCCAGGAGGCGGAGGUUGCAGUGAGGCGAGAUCACGCCACUACACUCCAGCCUGGCGACAGAGCAAGACUCUCUCAAAAAAAAAAAAAAAAAAUUUUUUUUUUAAAUGGGCUGGGCAUGGUGGCUUGUGCCUGUAGUCUCAGCAACUUGGGAGGCUUAAGUAGUAGGAUCGCUUGAGCCUGGGAGGUUGAGGCUGCAGUGAGCUGUGAUUGUGCCACUGUGCUUCAGCUUGAGUGACAGAGUGAGACCCUCCUGACUCAAAACAAAAAACAUGGUUUCUCCUCUCUCUCCUGUCUUCUUACUCUCUAUCCCAUUUGAUGUAGUGAUUUUUAAAUGCUUUUGUAAGUUAAUUCUUAACACAAAAGAGACAUUGUAAUGAGGCACACCACUAAAGUGAGCAUGCCCAAUUAAAACCAGUGUAAUAUAGGAUAAGAAAAUCUGAUUUUUCAAAAAAGAUACUCUACAUAAAGAAUCCUUCAUAUAAAAAGUUCUUUCUUGUAGUACAUUUAAAGUUUUAAUUCACUCAUGUAUAACUGAGAGUUCCUUUGAGCCCUUUUUAGGCAGGGAGGCAUGUCUGUCAUCUAGCGUGUGGCCCAGUAAGUGAUUAUUACAUUGGAAUCAGUUUUUCAGUCUUUUAAAAUAAAUUCUGUGCCAUAAGAAUAAAAGAUAAAGAGAAAAAUUAAUGUUAACUAUUUUUAGCUUAUUAUAACUAUGUCAACAAGUGUUUAUUAAUACCUAUUAUGGGAAAGUCACUGUGGUUGGCAUUGAAAAUUACAUCAUCUUUAAAGCAGUAUUUGUCCCCAGAUGGACUCAUCACUAGCAAAGACUAGGUUCAUUGGAAGGCAUAGGGUGAGAGAAUGGGAAGAUGAAGUGGAGGCGGGUUGUUAAAGUGCUGUCAGUGAGUGAUUUUGUCUACUUGAAUAAUGGUCCAUGUUUGGGGGCAUAUUGUGUUUCAUAAGAAGUGAAAGGUAUUUGCAAAGUAAGCUACAAAUGACCCAUAAAUCUGUUAACAACAGUCCUUAAUAUGCAAAGAUGAAAAACAAGCAUUACUGCUACCCAAAGGGAACUGGUGCUUGGUGAUGUGCAGAUGGGGCUGUUGGUUAAGAGAGCUAUUACAGGUUUUCUCUCUUAGGUUUCAUAGGAGGUAGUUACUGAGAUGAGAUUGUUUUAUCUUUUUGAAUACAGAUCUCUUGUCUUGAGUUAGUUCUGAGGAUGGGAGUAAUAAAGGAGUUUUUUGUUUUUUUGUUUGUUUGUUUGUUUUGGCUCCUUAGUAAUACUCCUCUGACAUUUAUUUCUAUUAUUCUUCAAAGAAAGGAAACCAACUGAAAUGUUUGCUUUAACAAACAUUUUAAUAAGUUCUCUGGGUUUUUUUUUCCCCUUUUAAAAAAAUUAGCAUAUACCAUAGCAAUAAAAGAACUAAUGUUAACUAUUGUAUGCUACAACUUAAGUGAUUUUUCUAAAGAAGCACAAUGUCAUUGAAAGUAUUAUUGAAAAGGAUCAUAGUCACAUUGAAUUUGUGAAGGCCAAAGAAAUUGAAGGGAGUGAUAUUUUCAUUUUAUGAUAUUCACAUAUUUAGUAAAUUUUGUGUACAAGAAUACCAGGCAGAGUGUUUUACCCAUGGAAACAGGUUUCAGAUUACUUUAUUUUUACUGUUAGAGUCUCAAGUUUAGAAAUGCUAACACUUAAAUCAGUUUUUUUCUCACUAUACUUGAAGAUUGUUAAUAUUUUGAUAUCUUCCUAGCUUGAUGAAUUUAAACAUAUCUUCAGAUCUGUGACAGUGACAGCCAAUAGGACUGAUAAUAUUAGCUUCAAACCAAUAAUAUCCAGGGUUAAAAUAAAAAUCAUAGUGAAAGUACGAUUGUAAAAUUAUGCUAUAUUAACUUUUAAGUCUGUAAUAACUUGACAUCAAAAUGUUAUGUAAUUACCAUAAAUAAUGGCUAGCGAGAACAUCUUUGGAAAUUCUCAAAUUACCUUUCUUACUACACUGUUUGCAGAAUGAAUGUAGAAAUGAUCCUGUUAGCUUUCUGAAUGUUCUGUGGUUGAAUGUGUUUUUGCUUAAAUAAAGCUUUUGGUAUUUGUUUAAAUUACACUUCUUGAGAAGUGGAAAUUUUAGGAUCAUCUUUGCUUUGUUUCAGUUUUGUGAUUUUUGAAAUGAAUGUUUAGUUUACUGAGCCAGUUGGUCAUUUCUUCCUCAUGUCGUUAAGUCCAGUGAGUAAGCCUGAACUGUGAAUAAAUUACCAAAAACUUGCUUAGAAUUUCAUUUUGAAGCAAUUUGCUAAUAUUUGAAGUGUAUACACAUUUGUAGUUAUGUUAGAAAUUGUAUUGUACUAAGAAUGUAAUCAAUGUCUACUUUAGUUGUAAACAUUUCUGAUGUCAAAACUUUAUUCAUUACUGUUGAUUUUAAGAAUAAGAAAUCACUGCCUAAAUAUUACCAAAAGCCACUGUCUCUACCCGAACUUCCCAGUUUGGGAAAGAAUCGUUAGAUAAAACAAAGGCUCUGCCCUUUCUGAUACCAAACUCCACAGAUACUUUCUCACAUCUUUUAAAACAUUUUGCAAUAACAUAUUGUUUAUAGGAAGUUUACGGGGUAUGCAAUGAUUAAAACUUUUAAGUGAAUUGAUAGUUGCAAAAGAAAGGAUAAUAUUUAAGGUCAGUGAGUAGCAAGACAAUCUAAAGUUUCUGUAAUAUCUGGCUCUCUGUUAAUUAUAGAGCAAAGUUUCCCUUACAGAAUCCUUUUAUGAACAGCAAGCUAGAGUCUAUCCCUAGUGGUUAUAGCACCUGCUGCGUUUUUCAGGAGACAGUUAGGCCAGGGUGAUUUGAAUGGAUAGAUGUGCUGUUUUGCCUGCUUGUAGAAUUCAGCCCAGUCUUUGGUCUCUCUCUCUCUCUCCCUCCUCCACCUCUCCCUCUCUCUUCUUCUGCACCAGAGCCUAAGGCUGCGCCACCAAGAUGCGUCAUUUUUUCCAGAGGCUUCUUUUUUUUUUUUUUGAGAUGGAGUUUUGCUCUGUUGCCCAGGCUGGCAUGCAGUGCUGCAAUCUUGGCUGACUGCAACUUCCACCUCCCGUGUUCACACGAGUCUUUUGCCUCAGCCUCUGGAUUAGCUGGGAUUACAGGCACGUGCCACCAUGCCUAGCUAAUUUUUGUGUUUUUAGUAGAGACGGGGUUUCACCAUGUUGGCCAGGCUAGUCUCAAACUCCUGACCUUAAGUGAUCUGCCCGCCUUGGCCUCCCAAAGUGCUGGGAUUACAGGCAUGAGUCACCGUGUCCUGCCCAGACAUAUCAAAUUUGACAGGUAUUGUAUACCCUUUGGAUCUUUAGGAAUUAAUUUUUGCCUCUGUCACUCAGCUUUGUAUAUUUUGAAAUGGAGAUAAGUAUAGGGAGGUCUUGGAAGGAAAAUUGCCAGAAUUCCCAAACCAUGUAACACUCAUUGAGAAUUCCAGAUCCAUUAUAUCUAAAGGGCAAGUGAAGGAAACAGUAUUGUGAACUGGGUAUAACUCCUUGGUUCUUAACUAGUACAUUCUUAAUCUGUGAGACCCAAAGGUUGAUAAACAAUAAUUUAAGAUUGUACAGUACUCUAAACGUCUGCAAAGGUCUAGAUGUUAUCAGUAUCACUAGUUUUUAUUUCUGCCAGUAGCUCCCUUUUAGGUUACAUUGUUGUCCUCUUUCCAGUGUCGCAUCUGUCAUUGGUUUUUCACUAUGGCAAGUUCAUUAAAAAGCUUGCUCCAUUGUUAUCUUCAAGUAAUGCCCAUAAGGAGAUGGAAGAUAUCUGAGACAAUUAAGGCUUUAGCUUCUAGGCAAGAGAAAUAACGUUGCAUUAAAUUUCAAGUUUCUUUCUGCUAGACUUGAAUGUGUCUAGCCACUCUAAUUUAUGGGGGCUUUUGGUUUUUUCCUAUUGUACUUUGUAUGUAGAAUUGUUUUGAAAUAUCAAGCAUAUUUACUUUGAAUUUGAACUCUUUCUUAAUUUUGUAUUUAUCCUUUGAAUAAAAUGUAAAUCCAA